AGAGAAGAGGAGGUUGGUGUGGAGCACAGGCAGCACCGAGCCUGCCCCGUGAGCUGAGGGCCUGCAGUCUGCGGCUGGAAUCAGGAUAGACACCAAGGCAGGACCCCCAGAGAGCUGGAGCUGCUGGUGAUGCCAGGCUGCCCUGUGCAGAUGCUGAAGCCUCUUUGGAAAGCAGCAGUGGCCCCCACAUGGCCAUGCUCCAUGCCGCCCCGCCGCCCGUGGGACAGAGAGGCUGGCACGUUGCAGGUCCUGGGAGCGCUGGCUGUGCUGUGGCUGGGCUCCGUGGCUCUUAUCUGCCUCCUGUGGCAAGUGCCCCGUCCUCCCACCUGGGGCCAGGUGCAGCCCAAGGACGUGCCCAGGUCCUGGGAGCAUGGCUCCAGCCCAGCUUGGGAGCCCCUGGAAGCAGAGGCCAGGCAGCAGAGGGACUCCUGCCAGCUUGUCCUUGUGGAAAGCAUCCCCCAGGACCUGCCAUCUGCAGCCGGCAGCCCCUCUGCCCAGCCUCUGGGCCAGGCCUGGCUGCAGCUGCUGGACACUGCCCAGGAGAGCGUCCACGUGGCUUCAUACUACUGGUCCCUCACAGGGCCUGACAUCGGGGUCAACGACUCGUCUUCCCAGCUGGGAGAGGCUCUUCUGCAGAAGCUGCAGCAGCUGCUGGGCAGGAACAUUUCCCUGGCUGUGGCCACCAGCAGCCCGACACUGGCCAGGACAUCCACCGACCUGCAGGUUCUGGCUGCCCGAGGUGCCCAUGUACGACAGGUGCCCAUGGGGCGGCUCACCAGGGGUGUUUUGCACUCCAAAUUCUGGGUUGUGGAUGGACGGCACAUAUACAUGGGCAGUGCCAACAUGGACUGGCGGUCUCUGACGCAGGUGAAGGAGCUUGGCGCUGUCAUCUAUAACUGCAGCCACCUGGCCCAAGACCUGGAGAAGACCUUCCAGACCUACUGGGUACUGGGGGUGCCCAAGGCUGUCCUCCCCAAAACCUGGCCUCAGAACUUCUCAUCUCACUUCAACCGUUUCCAGCCCUUCCACGGCCUCUUUGAUGGGGUGCCCACCACUGCCUACUUCUCAGCGUCGCCACCAGCACUCUGUCCCCAGGGCCGCACCCGGGACCUGGAGGCGCUGCUGGCGGUGAUGGGGAGCGCCCAGGAGUUCAUCUAUGCCUCCGUGAUGGAGUAUUUCCCCACCACGCGCUUCAGCCACCCCCCGAGGUACUGGCCGGUGCUGGACAACGCGCUGCGGGCGGCAGCCUUCGGCAAGGGCGUGCGCGUGCGCCUGCUGGUCGGCUGCGGACUCAACACGGACCCCACCAUGUUCCCCUACCUGCGGUCCCUGCAGGCGCUCAGCAACCCCGCGGCCAACGUCUCUGUGGACGUGAAAGUCUUCAUCGUGCCGGUGGGGAACCAUUCCAACAUCCCAUUCAGCAGGGUGAACCACAGCAAGUUCAUGGUCACGGAGAAGGCAGCCUACAUAGGCACCUCCAACUGGUCGGAGGAUUACUUCAGCAGCACGGCGGGGGUGGGCUUGGUGGUCACCCAGAGCCCUGGCGCGCAGCCCGCGGGGGCCACGGUGCAGGAGCAGCUGCGGCAGCUCUUUGAGCGGGACUGGAGUUCGCGCUACGCCGUCGGCCUGGACGGACAGGCUCCGGGCCAGGACUGCGUUUGGCAGGGCUGAGGGGGGCCUCUUUUUCUCUCGGCGACCCCGCCCCGCACGCGCCCUCCCCUCUGACCCCGGCCUGGGCUUCAGCCGCUUCCUCCCGCAAGCAGCCCGGGUCCGCACUGCGCCAGGAGCCGCCUGCGACCGCCCGGGCGUCGCAAACCGCCCGCCUGCUCUCUGAUUUCCGAGUCCAGCCCCCCCUGAGCCCCACCUCCUCCAGGGAGCCCUCCAGGAAGCCCCUUCCCUGACUCCUGGCCCACAGGCCAGGCCUAAAAAAAACUCGUGGCUUCCCGGUGCCUCUGUGUGAGUCCCGCGCGGGCGGCCCUUCAUCCUCUUGCCAAGGGCCCGCCUCUAUGCGCCCGCCCCUGCGAAACUGCGCCGCGCGACCGCCGUGGCAGCGCCUCAGCUAGCCCCGGGUCCGCGAGAACCUGGGGCGGGGCGGGGCGGGGACCAGACGGGCCUCCCAGGCGGAGCGAACCCUCCACCUCCCACCCCGCGCCGGGCUGCCGCGCUCCGGAACCCAAAUUCCCGCCCCGAGGCUGCCGGGGGAAGCGAGAGGCGCGGAGCCCACGCCCGGGACUCCAGCGGAGGAAACGCAGACCAAGGCGCAGCGCCGCGCACCCACCGCCAGGGGGCAGCUCCUACGGCGCCGGACAGGGGCGGCGCGGGAGGGGAGCGGGGCUGAGGGGACCGGGAGGGCGGGAGGGGACCUGCGACUGAGGGGACAGGGAGGGCGGGAGGCGACCCGCGGCUGAGUGAGGGAAGGGCGGGAGGGGACCCGCGGCUGAGGGGACCGGGAGGGCGGGAGGCGACCCGCGGCUGAGUGAGGGGAGGGUGGGAGGGGACCCGCGGCUGAGGGGACAGGGAGGGCGGGAGGGGACCCGCGGCUGAGGGGACCGGGAGGGCGGGAGGCGACCCGGGGCUGAGUGAGGGGAGGGCGGGAGGGGAGCGGGGCUGAGGGGACCGGGAGGGCGGGAGGGGACCUGCGACUGAGGGGACGGGGAGGAUGUGAGGCGAUCCGGGGCUGAGUGAGGGGAGGGUGGGAGGGGACCCGCGGCUGAGGGGACGGGGAGGGCGGGAGGGGACCCGCGGCUGAGGGGACGGGGAGGGCGGGAGGCGACCCGGGGCUGAGGGGACGGGGAGGGCGGGAGGGGACCCGCGGCUGAGGGGACAGGUCCUGCGUGCGGGCUGGGGAGACAGGCGGGCGAGGGUAGGGGUGCACAAGGCUGUGUGGUUUGUGGGCUGUUGUGCAGGGUGGGUCCAAGCAUGUGGGGGCAGGCUUGUCCUGGGGAUGCAGUGCCCAGGGUUGGUGGAUGGGGCUGAGAGGACCAGCAUUUGAGCUGGAGGGCAGGAAGGUGACUCCAGUCUGAGACCAGGACUUGGAUGCAGCUCCACUGGAACUCACCCUAUCCUGGGAGCCACCUGGGCACCUGUCCUGCAGAUGCAGGAUUUGAACCCAGGUUUGGCAACUCAGUUCCCACUCUUCUGCUAUGAAUGCUGGGUCAGAAGGAUUCUCAAAACACCCUGGCUUAUCUCACCUGAUGGUUCCUGACCAAGACCACAGGGUACCCUCCCCUGGUGGAGGUCCAUGGGGCCAUGCUAGGCUGGAGUUCAGGGAUGGCUCAGCGGUAUGAAGGAGCACUGGAUGCUGAAUGGACCCCAGGGUGCCCCGAAUGCUCUCCCGGUCUUGAGGCACCACUUUCCUACCCUUCUCUACUUCUCUCCUUUUCCUACCCUUCUCUACUUUUUUCUUUCCUACAUUUGUGUCCCUGCCACACUGUGAACUCAGCCAUAUCUUCCUCUUCCCUCUUUGCUUUGGGGAAAGCUAGCAAAGUUCAUCUCAGGUACAGUACAAGUUACUUUUCUGUUCGAUUAGUGACCUCAUACUUCCCCCAUCUAAAGGACACCUUAGACUUCAGCAUUCUGUCUGUGCAGAAAUCUCCUACACCCAUCCUGCCUCCCUGCCCAAGCUUGUGAAAAGCUUGCUGCAGAUGCUGCAGGGGGAUAGGGAUCCACAUAGCCCUGCAAGGCCUUCAGGAGCUUCUGGGGGCUGCUUUGUGUGUGAGCUGCACUUGGCCAAGCCAAGCUCUGGCAGUUGCAGUGGCUGCUCCCUGUGGCUUCCUAUCCCUCAUUCAUGCUCCAUAUCUCCUCAGUAACCAUCUGGCAAAAAGCUUCGUGGCAACACCUGGCUCAGAAGCCGAUAUCAUCCCAGACUAAGCUCUGCCCUCCAGGGUUGCACGUGUGGGUUUGCUCCCUGGUUCUUGGCCUUAUACCUGAAUGUGUCUCAGAGCACUUGGCCUGCUCUCUUGGCCUGCCAACUAUGUUCUAGGAGGGCUCUGUGCUCCAGGCUGUGAUUUGGACAACUGGCUGGUGGCCCUCAGCCAGUGAAAGGCCUCUUUCCACACACCUGGGGACUGGCAGUCACACCUCAGUGGCACUGACAGAGGCCUGCUUCAAGGCAGAUGCCUAUUCCAAAGGAAAUCCAGCUUGACAAGGCUUGGGAGACCCCAGGAGGGUGCCACAAUGUGGCCCCUUCUGGGCUAUAGCAGACAGACUCUAGAAUGGCUCCCUUGACCCCCACCUGCUGGUAUGCAUGCCCUUGUGUGAUCUCACCUUGAGUGUGUGCAGGACCUGUGCCUUGUUGUAACCAAUAGAAUACAGAGGUAAGGGGAUGUCACUCCUGUGACACCUUGUGAUCAUGUGACAUAAGAUUAUAACAUUAUCAAGGAAUAGCAGUCUAUCCCUUGCUAGCUUUAAAAAGUGAGCUGCUAGGCUAUGAGCUGUCCUAUGAAGAGGCCCAUGUAGCAGGGUACUGGGGUUGCCUCCAGCCCCCAACUAGCAAGAAACUGGGGCCCUCAAUCAUCCCAUCCACAAGGAGUUGAGUGUGGCUAGCAACAACGUGAGCUUCAGAAGUGGCUGCUUUCCUGGUCAUACCUGAAGGGGAGACCACAGCCCCAGCUGACAUCUUGAUUGUAGCCUAAUGGGACCUUGAGCAGAGAACCCAACAAAGCCACACUUGGGCUCCUGAUCCACAGAAACUGGGAGAUCAUAAAUGUGUGUUGUUUUAAGUUGCUAAUUUGUAGUGAUGUUCUUAUGCAGCAUAGAUAACUCAUACACAGAGAACCAAGGCCACGCGAGAACCCUGUGGGGGCCCCUGCUGCUCAGCCACUCCUCACAUGCUGGGACAGCUGUCUCUCUGGCCUCUAGCACCAAGGUCCCCACUAUCCCAGGCCUUGACUCUUGGAUCAGAGAGGGACAAAAGCCCCAUGGAGCCAAGCAGACUCCUCCCCCUGGGCUGCACUCACCUAGCUUGUCUGGCACACACAAGUUGGAGUAGAGAAGGCAGGAAGCCCUGGGAAGGGAGAGGGUGAUGGCCUUGCUUAACUGGGAUGAGUGUCCACCAAAUUUCCCUUCCCACUUCCCCUGCUCAUGAGCCCCCAGGGGACCUGUGUCAGUUCACUUUCUAGAGGCUUCUAUGUGCCCUAACUUGGAUGACACCCACGGGCCUCCCCAACUCAGCACAGGGAACAUAUGCCCAUGGUGGCAUGGGGAAAGAACCCAGCCUCUCCCCUGCCCAGGCUCCUGCACCCCAUAGCUGUCACCCCUCUGGAACCUCUCAGGGCAGCACGAGUGGUAGCCUCGGAGUGGCCUUCACCCUCCAGGCACUGCGGUCCUCCAGAUUGGCUCACAGCCCAGCUCUUGCUCCCAUAUCCACAGCCAUGAGAGCAGCCACCUCCCCAGGGGGCCAUAAGCGCUUCUCACCAGGAGCCCACCUAGGCCAGGAGGGAGCUGGGGGCAAGUUCCAACUGCCCCCUUGAACACUGCAUACCCAUGAAUCUGGCAGGGGCAUCUGGGAAGAGAUUUGACCACUGAAAGACUGUAGGGAAACCCUUGAACCUCAAUCCGCUACGCCACGUGGAUUUGCUUCCUGUGGGCUGCCCAAGAGCGCCUCUGUGGUGAAGGAAGCUUCUGAGGAUGGGCCACUAAAGAUGGCCAAGGUCACCUUUCUGUGCUGUCCCCACUCUGCACUCCAUCUCCCAUCCCACACUGCCUCCAGCUGGAGGGAGGGAGGGAGGGUUGUACGUCUGUGUCCCUGCCACACUGUGAACUCAGCCCUAUCUUCCUUGUCUUCCUCACAGCCUCUGGCUCAGAGGAGGACCUGGACAAAUGGAUGAUAGGUAGGCAACCACCCAAAUGUUCCUCAUUGACUGUUCUCUAGAGCUGCUUAGUAGAGACCAGGAGUGUGUGGGAGGAAAGCCCUGGUAAACUUCGACCCUGAGACAGAAGACCUCAGCAGCCUUCAGCAUGGGAUGCAGCACUUUCUUUAUUGCCCAUCCAGGGAACAGCCAAGCCAGCUCCAUCUGCAUUCUGGCUGCAGCGUGUACAUUAGGGGACUCAGGGGCCACAGUGUGGGACCGUGCACACUGGCAAGGCACUGGCGGAUGCUGGCAGGCCAGUGGACAUGGAUAGAUGAGAAUGACAACUCACAGAUGUCCUAGCUUCUGCUGGCCCAGCUGCCAGCCACUGGCCAUCACCCUUUUGCCCAGCAUGUGUGCAUUGUCACCCAAAACAUCUUGAAACUUGCCAUUAGUGAGGCAUUCAACAAAGAAGUAAGCUAAGUGAGUAGGAAACAGUGUUUCCUGGAAUAUACCGCACUCUGCCUGAAAUAGGAAAACUAUGUUUGCCGGGAAGCAGCAGCAGCAGGAAAGAAGUUAUACCAAAAACGACUUGUACACCACAGACAUUAUAACCCUUUCCUCAAAGAAACAGUCAUGUUCUGUUGGGUAUUAUGGACAGGUCUCUGGAAAUUUAUCUAAUAAAGACCAACAAACUUCCCCA